GGCUGGGCCUUUGUCUCUCGCUCCCACCAGAGCUUGGAAUCCGUCUCUGCUCUUCUGCAUUCUCCACCUCGGGAGCCCCUGGGGACUCUGUGACGGCCUCUGUUGCCCUGUGAUCUGCAGGUCCGGAGAGACGCACAGCUAAGAUGUCAGGACAUCCUGGAAGCUGGGAAAGGGUCUUGCCAUCUCUAAGCUGGACCUGGUGACCUUUUUGGAGGGAAAGAAAGAGCCCUGGACUGUGAAGAGUGAGGAGACCAUAGCUGCACAGCCAGAGUGAGUUGUUGCUCCCGCCUGAGCCCAGCCCCCAGAAAGGAUUGUGACAUAUCGUUGGACCCAGAAUUGAGAAGGCAUUGAGACAUGGCUGGGCUCAGCACUAAGAAGAUGUGAGUCCUCUGCCUGAAGCCUGACCACAGGGAGCAUUGUGACACAUUUCUUGACCCAUUACAAUCUCUUCUACGGGCAAAGCUGAGGUAAAUGCCCGUUUUACCUAUGUGAUGUGACAUUCCUCUUCUGCCUGGGCCAUGCCCACAGAAUAGAGUGACGUAUUGGUGGGGCAAGCAAAACAGUGGUGUAAUUAUUCUGCCUGGUCCCUGUACACAGGAGUCACUGUGAUACAUGUUUGGGCCUCCCACCUAGAUGAUGUGACUUUUUUCUUCUGGAGUUUGUCCACAGUGGGAAUUGUGAUAUGCCACGUGACAUAGCUCCUAUGUGAUGUGACUCUUUCUCAUUCUUGGCCUCUUUCCACUGGGGUUACUGGAACAUAAAGCUGAGCCCAGCUCCUAGGCUGUGUCUCUCCUUUCUAAGCCCUACCCACAAAGGACAUUGUGACGUAUCUCUAGGCUUCUCACCUAGGUAAUAUUACUUUUUUACCUAGGCCCACCCCUCAGGGGUAUUGUGAAAUACUGCUGGACCAACAUGCUAGAUGAUAGGAGUCUCUGCUACUGCUUGGGGUGUGAUUAAGAGGAAAUUGUGAUGUGCAUUUGGGUGCAUCCAGCACCUAAGUGAUGUUAACUCUCCUCUUGUGCCUGAGACCUGCAUGCAAUAUGUGUUUUUGUGUUUUUUGUUUGUUUUUGAGAUGGAGUUUUGCUCCUUUUGCCCAGGCUGGAUUGCAAUGGUGCAAUCUCAGCUCACCACAACCUUCAUCUCCCAGGUUCAAGCAAUUCUUCAGCCUCAGCCCCCUGAGUAUCUGGGAUUACAGGCAUGUGCCACCAAGCCCGGUUAAUUUUUCUAAUUGUAGUAGAGAUGGGGUUUCUUCAUGUUGGUCAGGCUGGUCUCGAACUCCCAACCUCAGGUGAUCCACCGACCUCAGCCUCCUAAAGUGCUGGGAUUACCGGUGUGAGCCACCGCACCUGGCUGGCAUCAUGUAUUUCAACAUGUCUCUGGGUCCAACAACAUUAUGAUGAGACUUUCCUGUGUGGGCUCUCACACAGAACUAUUCUAACACAUCUUUUCAUUCAUUAUCUUGGCGAUUUGACUUUUCUGUUCCGCUUGAGCACUGCCAAAAGAAAAAUUUGUGGCAGAUCACUGGACCUAGCACCUAGGUGAUGUGGCUCUUCUCACUUGCCUGAGACCUGCAUAUUUUGGUUAUUGUGACAUAUCACUGAAACAAACACCUAGGGGUUGGAAGGCUUCUGCCUGAGCCCCUCCCACAGAGGGCCUUGGAAUAUAUUUUUUUAUCCAUCACCUGGGAGAUGAAACCCUCUACUUCUACCUGCCUUCUUCCCAUAGAGAAGAUUGUGAUAUAUUGCUGGGCCCAGGAACCAGGUGUUUUGUCUAUCUUUUCUGGGCUUUGCCUACAGUGAGCCUUGUGACACCCAGGUGAUCAUACUCUUCUUCCUAUGCCCUGCUUUCAGGAGAGGAUUAUAACAUCUCUGGUUGAGAACUCUGUGAUGUGACUCUCCUUGCUGGUGCAUGCUGUCAGGGAAGAUUGUGACAUAACCCUGGCUCAGCACACAGUUGAUGUGACUCUUGUGCUUGUUCUCUACCCACAGGUGGAAUUGUGACAUAUAACUUGGCCAAGCACACAGAUGUAAUGGUGUGGUGACUCUCAUACCUAGAACUGGGACCUGUGCAGGAUUGUUAAUUCAUUACUGGACAUUCCUGUGGGUGUGAUUGUUACAUAUGCCUAUGUUCAGCACCCGAGUGAUUUGAUUUUGCUGCCUGGUCUCAGUCCAAAUGUAAGAUUGUGAUUUAUCGCUGAAUCCAGCACCUCGGUGAUUUGACUCUCCCUUUUUUUGUGGGAGGGAUCCUGCAAAUUUUGGGUAUUGUCAAUUAUUGCUGAAUCCUGUACCCAUGUUAUGACUCUCCCAAAUGUGCCUUACCUGUUGUGGCACAAUAUAUCACAUUAGACAUUGUUAAAUAUUGUUGGGUUCAACACCUGGGUGAUGGAUGUAACUUUUUUUCUGGGCCUGCCUACAGGGGACCUUGUGACAUAACUCAAUGCCCAUCAUCAUGGUAAUGUUACUCUCUUCUCCUGCCUGAUCUCUGCUCACAGAGAAAUUGUGACACAUCACUGGCCUAGCAUCUAGGUGAUGUGACUCUCCUCUUUUUUUCAGGCUCUGCAUAUUUGGGUAUUGUGACAUAUUGCUGAACUCAACACCUAAGGGAUGGGAGUCUCCUACCUAGGCCCUUCCUACAGGGGACAUUGUGACAUGUCUCUGCAUUCCUCAUCCAGGAGAUGUGACUCUCCUUUUCUGCCUACACCCUGCCUACACAGAAAGUUGUGGCAUAUUGCUGUGGUCAGCAACCAGAUGAUAUAUUUCUCCUGCCUGGGUCUUUAUUACAGGAAAGAUGAUUGACAUAUUACUGGGCCCAGCAUCCAGAUGAUGUGACUCUCUUCUUCUGUUGGUCCUUGCUUACAGGGAAACUGUAGCAUAUUGCUACACCCAACACCUAGCUUAUGUGAUUCUUCUUUUAGGUUUGCCUUCAGGGAACAUUGUGACAUAUUGCUGGGCCCUGCACUGAUAAUUUGUGACUCUUCUGCCUGUGAUUUGCCCACUUGGGGCAUUGUGACAUAUUGCUGGGUUUAACACUCAGGUGAUGUAACUUUUAUGCCUAGGCCUUGCUUACAGGAGGCAUUUUGAAAUGUCUUUGUGGCUGGGCAUGGUGGCUCAUGUCUGUAAUCCCAGCGCUUGGGGAGGCCAAGGUGGGCAGAUCACAAAGUCAGGAGUUCGAGACCAGCCUGGUCAACAUGGUGAAAACCUGUCUCUACUAAAACAAAACAAAACAAAACAAAACAAAACAAAACAAAACAAAACAAAACAAAUAAAACCACAAAAAUCAGCCAGGUGUGGUGAUUGGUGCCUGUAGUUGCAGCUACUCAGGAGGCUGAGGCAGGAUAAUCGCUUAAGUCCAGGAGGUGGAGGUUGCAGUGAGCUGAGAUUGCACCACUGCACUCCAUCCUGGGCAACAGAGUGAGACUCCAUCUCCAAAAAAAAUAAAAUAAAAUAAAAUAAAAAUACAAAUGUCUUUGCACCAAUCCUACAGGUGAUGUGACUCUCUUGUGUUACCUGGUCUCUGCCCCCAGGAAGAAUUGUGACCUUUCACAGCGUAUAGCUAAUUUUUUUCUUUUAUUUCUUAGUUUUUCUCCUGCAGGAAAGAUUGUGAAAUAUUACUGAACUAAGCACCAAAGGGAUAUAUUUUUUUUCUUGGACCUGCCCAUGUAAGACCUUGUGACAUAUUGCUGGGCCCUACACCUAGAUGAUGGACUGUUGACAUUUAGGGAUGUGGCCAUAGAAUUCUCUCUGGAGGAGUGGCAACACCUGGACAUUGCACAGCAGAAUUUAUAUAGAAAUGUGAUGUUAGAGAACUACAGAAACCUGGCCUUCCUGGGUAUUGCUGUCUCUAAGCCAGACCUGAUCACCUGUCUGGAACAAGGGAAAGAGCCCUGGAAUAUGAAGCGACAUGAGAUGGUGGAUGAACCCCCAGGUAUGUGUCCUCAUUUUGCUCAAGACCUUUGGCCAGAGCAGGGCAUGGAAGAUUCUUUUCAAAAAGCAAUACUGAGAAGAUAUGGAAAAUAUGGACAUGAGAAUUUACAGUUAAGAAAAGGCUGUAAAAGUGUGGAUGAGUAUAAGGUGAACAAAGAAGGUUAUAAUGGACUUAACCAGUGUUUCACAACUGCCCAGAGCAAAGUAUUUCAAUGUGAUAAAUAUUUGAAAGUCUUCUAUAAAUUUUUAAAUUCAAACAGACCUAAGAUAAGACAUACUGAAAAGAAAUCUUUCAAAUGUAAAAAACGUGUCAAAUUAUUUUGCAUGCUUUCACAUAAAACCCAACACAAAAGCAUUUAUCAUAGAGAGAAGUCCUACAAAUGUAAAGAAUGUGGAAAAACCUUUAAUUGGUCCUCAACCCUUACUAAUCAUAGGAAAAUUUAUACUGAAGAGAAACCUUACAAAUGUGAAGAAUAUAACAAAUCUCCUAAGCAACUCUCAACCCUUACUACACAUGAAAUAAUUCAUGCUGGAGAGAAACUCUACAAAUGUGAAGAAUGUGGUGAAGCUUUUAAUCGAUCCUCAAAUCUUACUACACAUAAGAUAAUUCAUACUGGAGAGAAACCUUACAAGUGUGAAGAAUGUGGCAAAGCAUUUAUCUGGUCCUCAACCCUUACUGAGCAUAAGAAAAUUCAUACUAGAAAGAAACCCUACAAGUGUGAAGAAUGUGGCAAAGCAUUUAUAUGGUCCUCAACACUAACUAGACAUAAGAGGAUGCACACUGGAGAGAAACCCUACAAAUGUGAAGAAUGUGGCAAAGCUUUUAGCCAGUCCUCAACCCUUACUACACAUAAGAUAAUUCAUACUGGAGAGAAACGCUACAAAUGCUUAGAAUGUGGCAAAGCUUUUAAGCAACUCUCAACUCUUACUACACAUAAAAUAAUUCAUGUUGGAGAGAAACUCUACAAAUGUGAAGAAUGCGGCAAAGGUUUUAAUCGAUCUUCAAAUCUUACUACACAUAAGAUAAUUCAUACUGGAGAGAAACCUUACAAGUGUGAAGAAUGUGGCAAAGCAUUUAUCUGGUCCUCAACCCUUACUAAACAUAAGAGAAUUCAUACUAGAGAGAAACCCUACAAAUGUGAAGAAUGUGGCAAGGCAUUUAUAUGGUCCUCAACCCUAACUAGACAUAAGAGGAUGCACACUGGAGAGAAACCCUACAAAUGUGAAGAAUGUGGCAAAUCUUUUAGCCAAUCCUCAACCCUUACUACACAUAAGAUAAUUCAUACUGGAGAGAAACCCUACAAAUGUGAAGAAUGUGGCAAAGCCUUUAACUGGUCCUCAACUCUUACUAAACAUAAGAUAAUUCAUACUGAAGAGAAACCCUACAAAUGUGAAAAAUGUGGCAAAGCCUUUAAGCAGUCUUCAAUCCUUACUAACCAUAAGAGAAUUCAUACUGGAGAGAAACCCUAUAAAUGUGAAGAAUGUGGCAAAUCUUUUAACCGGUCUUCAACUUUUACUAAACAUAAGGUAAUUCAUACUGGAGUAAAACCCUACAAAUGUGAAGAAUGUGGCAAAGCAUUUUUCUGGUCCUCAACCCUAACUAAACAUAAGAGAAUUCAUACUGGAGAGCAACCCUACAAAUGGGAAAAAUUUGGCAAAGCCUUUAAUCGGUCCUCGCACCUCACCACAGAUAAGAUAACUCAUUGGAGAGAAAUCUUACAAGUAUGAAUAAUGUGCCAAAGCCUAAGAAAACCCUCAAUUCUUAAUAGAUAUAAGAUUAUUCCUACUGGAGAGAAACUACAAACCUGAGAGAGGCGCUAAUGCUUUUGACAGUACCUAAAACUUUAAAGAAAAUCAUUCUGCUGAAAAAUCCUAGAAAUGUGAAGAAUGUGAAAAAGCCUUUAAAUGAUUGUCACACUUGAUUGUAGGUAAGAUAAUUCAUACUGGAGAAAACUACCAGUGUGAACAACGUGGCCAAGCUUCGACAAUGCUCACACCCUAUUGCACAGGAAAGCAUUUAUACUUGAGAAGAAAUGUACAAAUAUUGGCAAAGUAAAAAAUCCAUUAACACCUGCUCACAUCUUACUCAAAAUUGUAGAGUUCAUAGUAAAUAAAAGCAUUAAAAUUCUAAUUACUCUCAGAAGAUCUGUCAGAAAGUAUGUCUUUAAAGUAUAGAAGAGCAUUUAUUUUGAAAAAAACAUUACACAUAUGAAGAGGAUUGUAAUAUCUUUACUUGUACCACAGAUCUUAUUGUACACAUUUUAUACUAGAGAAAAACCCUCAGGCAGUUGUUAAAAUUUUGUUGAACAUCAGGGAGUUUAAGAAAACCCUGCAAGUAUAAUGAAUUUGGAAAAACAUUUUUUCAAAAACUACAAAUUAUAAAACACCAAAGUGUUCAUACUAAAAUAUAUUUUUGCAGAUACAUUAAAUAUGAAAGAUAUUCAAUCCAAAAUUAAGUCUAUGUAAAUAUCAGGGAAUAAUUCACAGUAGAAAUAUCUAGGGCAUUCAAGCUUUAGACAUUACACUAAAUCAGAGUGCUGAGUAUAGAAAAUAAUACAAACAGAUUUGUCUAAACAUUUGUAUAUAACUUUAAAAAUAGAAUAUUUUUUGGAGGGUUAUAAUUACAUUCAAAGUACUUUUUUUUGAAAAUACAGAUUUUUUUUAAAAGUGAAUAAUGUGUUCAACUCUUAAAUUCAUGCUGUUUCAUCAUUGCUGGUGUAUUCAUAUGUGAAAGCAUGUGACUAAUUGUUGCUGCAUAAAAGAUAUGAGAUUCUUUUUUAUUAGGCAUUAUUUAUGACCUUUUCUAUGAAAAGAUAAGGACAUUAAAAUGUAAGAUGCGUGAGGAAAAUUUAGGUAGAGAGGCUCUUUGUGGUUAACUUAUAAUAUUGAGUGAUGCAUGAGGUAGGUGUUCAGAAUAAUAUUCCUCUGCAUUAUUAUGAAUGAAAAGCAUUCUUAAUUUUAGUUAAAAUUAAGUUAGUCAUAUGUUAUUUUAUUAAUUGUACUUCUAUGAAAUAAUAUGCAGUCUAUUUUUAAAUUAUAAAUUAUGUGUGAACUUAGCUUUUCAAUUCAACAUUUUUAACAUAUUAAAUACUAUUGUGAAUUCAAUGAAGUGUUCUUAUGCCACUAACUUUAACCUAUUCCCUUACUCAAGGAUGUAGGUAAAAGAUGGUAACAAUACACUAUUUGGUAAGAUAAUGUACUGACAUCUCUAGCAAUCUUUUUUGCCAGUGGCUUUAAAUUGCCAAUAAGUUAAAGAAUAUUGUUCCUAUGGGUUAAAUUUUUAUUCUUAUUUUCACAUUUAAAUUUAUUUUUCUUAAUUUUUGUGGAUACAUAAUAUGUGUAUAUAUGUAUGCCAUAUAUGGUAUAUUUUGAUGCAGGCAUACUCUAUAUAAUAAUCACAUUAGAGGAAAUGAGAUAUCCAUUACCUCUAGCAUUUAUUCUUUUUAUUACAAGCAAUUCAAUUGUACACUUUUAGUUAUUUUUAAAUUUACAAUGUUAUUGAUUACAGGGUCAUUUUUAUGGUCAUAAUAAAAAAUUUUAUACAAACGUGUAAAAUCUAUACAUUUCUGAGUUCUGAAUAAAUAUUUUUAAAAAUUUUAAUAUAUUUUUCUUUGAAUAUGUGACCUUUGCCUGCAAGCACAUAUGGACUCUUAGAAUUGAUUUACAUAAAAUUAAAUAUAUACUUCUAUUAAAGAUAAACCUUAGGUGUAAAUAAA